GAAUACCAGUUUCCGAGCGGCAAGGCAGCGAUGGCGAUUUUUAGUGUGUAUGUGGUGAACAAAGCUGGCGGCUUGAUUUACCAGUUGGACAGCUACGCGCCACGGGCUGAGGCUGAGAAAACUUUCAGUUAUCCGCUGGAUCUGCUGCUCAAGCUACACGAUGAGCGUGUGUUGGUUGCUUUCGGCCAGCGGGACGGCAUCCGAGUGGGUCAUGCAGUGCUGGCCAUCAAUGGCAUGGACGUGAAUGGCAGGUACACGGCCGACGGGAAAGAGGUGCUGGAGUAUCUGGGUAACCCUGCUAAUUACCCGGUGUCCAUUCGAUUUGGCCGGCCCCGCCUCACUUCUAAUGAGAAGCUUAUGCUGGCCUCCAUGUUCCACUCGUAAGUCCCCCGUCUCCUGAACGGCAGCGCUUGUAAUUUGUCUACCUUUUCUUAAAUCGUCGUUCUGGUGUUAUGAAAAACGCAACCGAUCCAGAUCUAGAUUUUAGGCUCUUUGCCAUCGGCUCCCAGCUGUCUCCUGAACAGGGAAGCUCAGGCAUUGAGAUGCUGGAGACAGACACAUUCAAAUUGCACUGCUACCAGACACUGACAGGGAUCAAGUUUGUGGUUCUAGCAGAUCCUAGGCAAGCUGGAAUAGAUUCUCUUCUCCGAAAGAUUUAUGAGAUUUACUCAGACUUUGCCCUCAAGAAUCCAUUCUAUUCCUUAGAAAUGCCUAUCAGGUGUGAGCUCUUUGACCAGAACCUGAAGCUAGCUCUGGAGGUGGCAGAGAAGGCUGGAACUUUUGGACCUGGGUCAUAGGCUGAACCUGUUAUGGACCCCCAAAUUCUGAGAGUUCCUGCAACAAGAAUACUGCUGUUGACACUCCAGUGGAAAUCCCAGCAGCCUUGUUAGUGCACUUGAAAGUGGGAGAAUGCUGACCCUGAUGACUUGUACUGAUUCCUGAGCCUUAACACUGUGCUCUUUCCUUCUGUAUAUACCAUGGUCUUACUUUCCAACUCUGUACAGAUUUAUUUAUGGAGGAGCUAGGUCCAUAAAUGUUGUAAUAAAUAUUCCUUUGAUCUUGGUGUUUGCAAUCUGUCUUAAUCGAUGGUUUUGGGGGAAAGAUACAGGAAGUGAGUCAAAAAUGGUUAGGGAAUUCUGGGAAGAUGAUUAUGUGCUAGUAAAAAACAUAACAAAUAUGUGUUCAUUAAAUAAAUGAACAUAAGAUUUUGAAGCAUGAGCAUUGGAUCUAGUCCCAGAAUUGCUGCUGAUUUCCUGGGGUCCUGGGGUGGUGGCAGCAGUGGUGGUGGCUGUUAUGAUGAUGAUGAUGAUGGAACAUAUUUCAAGCACUUACAGCCAGGCAUUCCUGCUUUAUCUCACUUGAUCUUCACCCUAACUCCAGGGGGUACAUUCUGUUACAGAUAAGAGAUUUAGCAGACUUUCUGCCUCAAAGUUUCCAAGCUAGUUACUGACAGUCUGGGUUUGAACCAGGCUUUCUGGCUACACACUCAGUAAACCACUGUUACACUUCUUCCCUCCAUCAAGUUAUUUAAU